AGACGCCUGCAGACCAUCCCAGACGCCGGAGCCCGAGCCCCGACGAGUCCCCGCGCCUCAUCCGCCCGCGUCCGGUCCGCGUUCCUCCGCCCCACCAUGGCUCGGGGCCCCGGCCUCGCGCCGCCACCGCUGCGGCUGCCGCUGCUGCUGCUGGUGCUGGCGGCGGUGACCGGCCACACGGCCGCGCAGGACAACUGCACGUGUCCCACCAACAAGAUGACCGUGUGCAGCCCCGACGGCCCCGGCGGCCGCUGCCAGUGCCGCGCGCUGGGCUCGGGCAUGGCGGUCGACUGCUCCACGCUGACCUCCAAGUGUCUGCUGCUCAAGGCGCGCAUGAGCGCCCCCAAGAACGCCCGCACGCUGGUGCGGCCGAGUGAGCACGCGCUCGUGGACAACGAUGGCCUCUACGACCCCGACUGCGACCCCGAGGGCCGCUUCAAGGCGCGCCAGUGCAACCAGACGUCGGUGUGCUGGUGCGUGAACUCGGUGGGCGUGCGCCGCACGGACAAGGGCGACCUGAGCCUACGCUGCGAUGAGCUGGUGCGCACCCACCACAUCCUCAUUGACCUGCGCCACCGCCCCACCGCCGGCGCCUUCAACCACUCAGACCUGGACGCCGAGCUGAGGCGGCUCUUCCGCGAGCGCUAUCGGCUGCACCCCAAGUUCGUGGCGGCCGUGCACUACGAGCAGCCCACCAUCCAGAUCGAGCUGCGGCAGAACACGUCUCAGAAGGCCGCCGGUGACGUGGAUAUCGGCGAUGCCGCCUACUACUUCGAGAGGGACAUCAAGGGCGAGUCUCUAUUCCAGGGCCGCGGCGGCCUGGACUUGCGCGUGCGCGGAGAACCCCUGCAGGUGGAGCGCACGCUCAUCUAUUACCUGGACGAGAUUCCCCCGAAGUUCUCCAUGAAGCGCCUCACCGCCGGCCUCAUCGCCGUCAUCGUGGUGGUCGUGGUGGCCCUCGUCGCCGGCAUGGCCGUCCUGGUGAUCACCAACCGGAGAAAGUCGGGGAAGUACAAGAAGGUGGAGAUCAAGGAACUGGGGGAGUUGAGAAAGGAACCGAGCUUGUAGGUACCCGGCGGGGCAGGGGAUGGGGUGGGGUACCGGAUUUCGGUAUCGUCCCAGACCCAAGUGAGUCACGCUUCCUGAUUCCUCGGCGCAAAGGAGACGUUUAUCCUUUCAAAUUCCUGCCUUCCCCCUCCCUUUUGCGCACACACCAGGUUUAAUAGAUCCUGGCCUCAGGGUCUCCUUUCUUUCUCACUUCUGUCUUGAAGGAAGCAUUUCUAAAAUGUAUCCCCUUUCGGUCCAACAACAGGAAACCUGACUGGGGCAGUGAAGGAAGGGAUGGCAUAGCGUUAUGUGUAAAAAACAAGUAUCUGUAUGACAACCCGGGAUCGUUUGCAAGUAACUGAAUCCAUUGCGACAUUGUGAAGGCUUAAAUGAGUUUAGAUGGGAAAUAGCGUUGUUAUCGCCUUGGGUUUAAAUUAUUUGAUGAGUUCCACUUGUAUCAUGGCCUACCCGAGGAGAAGAGGAGUUUGUUAACUGGGCCUAUGUAGUAGCCUCAUUUACCAUCGUUUGUAUUACUGACCACAUAUGCUUGUCACUGGGAAAGAAGCCUGUUUCAGCUGCCUGAACGCAGUUUGGAUGUCUUUGAGGACAGACAUUGCCCGGAAACUCAGUCUAUUUAUUCUUCAGCUUGCCCUUACUGCCACUGAUAUUGGUAAUGUUCUUUUUUGUAAAAUGUUUGUACAUAUGUUGUCUUUGAUAAUGUUGCUGUAAUUUUUUAAAAUAAAACACGAAUUUAAUAAAAUAUGGGAAAGGCA